GGAAGGCAGGCUGCAGCAGGUGCCGGGUGCCACAUUAGACAUGACACUGUGCCGAAGCGAGUGCCACUUGUCUGCAGGGCCGUACCGCGGAACCCUCUUUGCCGACCAGCCAGCGAUGUUUGUCUCGCCUGCCAGCAGCCCCCCAGUGGCCAAGCUCUGUGAACUAGUCCACCUGUGCGGAGGCCGGGUCAGCCAAGUCCCCCGCCAGGCCAGCAUCGUCAUCGGGCCCUACAGCGGAAAGAAGAAAGCCACAGUCAAGUAUCUGUCUGAGAAAUGGGUCUUAGAUGGAGUCUCGCUGUGUCACCAGGCUGGAGUGUGCAGUGAUGAGAUCUCAGCUCACUGCAACCUUCACCUCCUGGGUUCAAGUGAUUCUUCUGCCUCAGCCUUCCCAGUAGCUGGAAUUACAGGCCCCGCCACCAUGCCCAGAUUCCAUCACCCAGCACAAGGUCUGUGCCCCUGAAAACUACCUAUUGUCACAAUGACAGUGACCUCACUGGCCUGUGGUGACUGCACACAGCUCGCAAAACUGUCUUUGGAUGUUCAAAUGAGAAACAAAACUGUGAAGAGAAGGAACUGGCGUAUACAAGAUGACUUCUGAUAUCAUGUUUGCCAUGUGUUGUGGUUCUUAAGAACUCAUAGGUGACUUUCUGAUGACUGAAUGUCUGUUUCAGAGACGCUUCGGGCCUUUUUAUUUUUAUUUUAUUUUUUAUUUUUUGAGACGGAGUCCUGCCCUGUUUCCCAGGCUGGAGUGCAAUGGCACAAUCUCGGCUCACUGCAACCUCCACCUCCCAGGUUCAAGCGAUUCUGCUGCCUCAGCCUCCUGAGUAGCUGGGAUUACAGAUGUGUGCCACCAUGCCUGGCUAAUUUUUGUAGUUUUAGUAGAGACAGGGUUUCGCCAUGUUGGCCAGGCUGGUCUCAAACGCCUGAGCUCAGGUGAUCUGUCAGGCCUCUUCUAUAGAAUUCCAGUCUUUGUGUCUUAGUCAUGAUCAUAAUUGAAAGGUCACAGAACCUUUGUCAUUAGAGCACAGUACUGCCAAAUAAAGAAUGGAAAUUCAAUGACAUUGUUUUAUUACUGAGAACAACUAGAGAACUCUGCAAGUUUCUUGGCUUAGACUCGAUCUUUAUUAAUACAUUAUCUAUUAGGUAGGAAAGACAUUUGUCAGCUAUUAAGGUGACUUUUAUCUAGCGGAGAUUCCUCUCUUAAAGUAAUGAAAGGAGAUAGGUAUGGGGGGUGUUAUACAGGAUAAUUGGUGACAUCUGAGUGUCUUACUUCUGCAAGCCUGCUUUAUGGUGAGCAAAGCAUCACCAGCAAGUGAUCACAAUGUCCACUGGCCGCUUUUUGCCUGCCGUCCUCGAGAUGAAAUUGGCAGUUGGGGCUGAUUCACAGAAACACCGAUUUGUGGCUGAGCACGGUGGCUCACACCUGUCAUCCCAGCCCUUUGGGAGGCUGAGGUGGACAGAUCACUUGAGGUCAGGAGUUCGAGACCAGCCUGACCAACGCAGCAAAACCCAUCUCUACUAAAAAUACAAAAAUCAGCUGGGUGUGGUGGCACACACCUGUGGUCCCAGCUCCUCAGGAGUCUGAGGCAGAAGAAUCGCUUGAACCCAAGAGGCAGAGGUUGCAGUGAGCCAAGGUUGCAGUGAAUCAAGAUUGCUCCACUGCACUCCAGCCUGGGCAACAGAGUAACUCUCCUUCUCAAAUAAAUAAAUAAAUAAAUAAGAAACACUGAUGUGUCUGUCACCUUCUAAAGAAAUGAAAUGCUAGGAAGUCCUAGCCAGAGUGAUCAGGCAAGAAUAAGCCAUAAAAGGCAUCCAAAUAGGAAAAGAAGUCAAACUGUCUCUCUUCACUGCCGAUAUGAUUCUAUACCUAGAAAACCCUAAAGACUCUGCCAAAAGGCUCCUGGAACCGAUAAAUGACUUAAGUAAAGUUUCAGGAUAGUAAAUCCAUGUACAAAAAUCAGCAUUUCCAAACACAGUAACAUUCAAGCUGAGCACCAAAUCAAGAACGCAAUCCCAUUUCCAAUAGCCACGGAAUGAAAUACCUAGGAACACGUAUAACCAAGGAGGCAAAGGAUCUCUACAAGGAGAACCAUAAACGAGAUGCUGAGUCCCAGCGAGGUCGGAGGUGCCACUGAGCCCUCAUCGUGGUGCCGUUCCCGCUCUGGGUUAUUUAUCUGUUGCUCAUCUCAGCUGUUGUUCCUACCUCAAAUUUCAAGUCCCUCAACAAAUAUAACAGAACCACUUCUAGAAUGAACCUUUGAGAAGGGAGGUAGCAGUGCAUUGUAUAGGAAUUGGCAUUCUAUAGAAAACCACAGAAACUGGAAAUAAUGAAGGGUUGUCUCUUGGUUUUAAAAUAAUGUAUACACCUAAAUCAUCCCCUUAUGAUACUCAUCCUCUAACAGCAAUUGAACUUCAAUACAAUGAGUCAUUCCUGAGUUCACUCGCUUCACAUUACAUAUGUUUCUCUAUAACCACAAGCAUCCUGGCUUGGUAGUGCUCCCACAGCACCAAAAAUCCCUGAGGAGGCUGACAAACAUUGUGCUGACUCAUGCUGGAGACAAGCCACAGAGAACUUCCAUCCCCCACCACAUCAGCCACGGAGCCAGCCCAGCCUCUGCCCACCCAGGCCUCAGUCCCCAGUGUUAAGUUCUGAUCCCUGAUGCUGGCCUGCCAGUGGCCAGUCAAGAUUCUCUUUCUGAAAGCUAGUAUUUUAUGAGGACUGACUGUUGCUAGACAUUACACUAAGCACAUUAUAUGUUGUACUUCAUUUUACCCUUUCAACAAUCCUAUUAGUAGCUUACUGUGGGUCUGCAAAGCCUUACUCAAAACAUAUAGGGCUAGAGGUUCUCAGGAUUCUGAAUUUUAAAAAAAAUUUGUAAAGGCUUAUGGCUCUCACCACUGUUAUUCAACGUUGCAUUAAAGUUUCUACCCAGAGAAGGCAAUAAAAGGAAAUUAAAGCUAUACAGAUUGGAAGUGAAGAAAUAAAAGUCUUUAUUCUCAAGAAUACAAGACACUAUGUAUAGAAAUUGUAAGGAAUGCAAAAAAAAAAAAAAAAAAAAGCCCUACAAGAACUUAUAACAAGUUUAGCAAGAUUGCAAUAUACAAUCUUGCAAUCUUCCUAAAGAUUAUAUACAAACCUAACAGAAUUGUAUUUAUAUAUACUGUCAAUAAGCAAUUCAAAAUGAAAUUAAGACCACGAUUCCAUUUAAAAUUGCAUCUAAAAAUAAACAAAAUAGGAAUAGACUUGGCAACAGUUGUAACAUCUGUAUACUGAAACCUGUAAAACAUUGCUGAAAGAAGUUAAAGACUUCUUUAAAUAGAGACAUAUACAAAGUUCAUAGAUUAGAAGAUGCAAUAUUGUUAAGAUGAUAGUCCUCAAAUUGACGUAUAGAUUCAAUGCAAUCCAUUAAAAUCUCAGAUGGCUUUUUAUAGAAUUUGAAAAGCUGAUGCUAAAUCUUUUAUGAAAAUGCAAAGAACCUCUAGUAGACAAAACAAUUUUUUUAAGAGCAAAGUUGGAGGAUUUAUAGAACCUGAUUCCAAAACUGUCAGUAAAACUACAAUAAUUACAAAGUAUCAGCCAGGUGCCGUGGCUCACAUCUGUAAUACCAGCUCUCUGGGAGGCUGAGGCGGGUGGAUCACUUGAAGUCGGGAGUUUAAGACCAGCCUGGCCAACUUGGUGAAACCUUGUCUCUACUAGAAAUACAAAAAAUUAGCCAGGCAUGAUGGCACACACCUGUAAUCUCAGUUACUCAGGAGGCUGAAGCAGAAUAGCUUGAACCCAAGAGAGUCCAGCUCAAAAACAACAACAAGAACAAAAGUAUCACAUUGGCAUAAGAAUAGACAUGUAAAUCAAAUAACAAAAUAGAGAAUUCAGGUAUAAAUCUUCAUAUUUAUGGCUGAUUGACUUUGAACAAAGGUGACGAGGCAAGUCAGUAUAGCAGCAUAUUCUUUUCAACAAAUGGUGCUGGCAGAAGAAAAAAAAAGUACUUGGAUCCUUACCUCACACCAUGCACAAAAAUUAGCUCAACGUGGACUAUAUCAGGGUUUCUCAACAUCAGCAGUGUUGGCGUUUGCUGGGGUGGAUAAUUCUUUCCUGUGGAGAGCUGUCCUGUGCACUGUAGAAUGUUUAGCUGCAUCCUGGCCUCUGCCUAUUAGAUGCCAGUGGCAUCCCUCCCCUGACACACACCUAGUUUUGACAAUCUCUGUCUCCAGAUAUUCCCAAAUGUGCCCUGGAGAGCAAAACUGUUUCCAGUUGAGAACCAUUGACCUAAUGUAAAAAAUAAAAUGUACAGAAGAAAGCAUAGCAGGAAAUCAUUCUGACCUCAGGUUAGGCAAAGCUUUCUUAGAUAUGACACUAAAGGCAUAAUUCAUUAAAAAAAUAAGUUGGGCUUUGUCAAAAUUUUAAGUUUUGCUCUUCUGAAGAAACCAUUAAAAAAAAAUGAAAAGACAAGCCACAGACUAUGAAAAAAUACUUGCAAAUCAUAUAUCUGAUAAAGGACUUGUACCCAGACCAUGUAAAGAACUCAUAACUCAUUAAUAAAAGGAUAAAGAAAAAGCUGAAGACAAUUCAUGCAAGAAGAUAUACAAAUAUUAAGCACAUUAAAAUGCUCAAUAUUAUUAGUCACUAGGGAAAUACAAAUUAAAGGCCCAAUGAAAUACCUAUUACACACCCAUUAGAAUGACUGUAAACAACAAGACUGAUAAUUCCAACAUCUGACCAAGAUAUGGAGAAACUAGAACUCUCCUACAUUGCUGGCAUGAGUGCAAAAUGAUACAGCCACUUUGAAACACCAUUUGGCAGUUGCUUAAAAAAUUGAACAUUCAACUACCAUAUGACCCAGCAAUUUCACUCUCAGGUAUAUAACCAAAAUACAUGAAAACAUGGAUCUGCACAAGGUCUUGUAUACAAAUGUUCAUAGCAACAUUAUUCAUAAUAACCAAAAAUUAGCCCAUCAACUGAAAAGUAGAUAAACAAAAUGUAUAUCCACACCAUGGAACGCUACUCAGCAAACUUCUAAAAAGCAACAAACUACUAAACACGUGCAACAACAUGAAUGAGCCUCAGAAACAUAAGUGAAAGAGGUCAGACACAAAAGACUACAAAUUGUAAGAUUCCAUUUAGAUACCAUUUCUACAAACCGCAAAACUGUAGAGGCACGAAACAGAUUCAUGGUCUGCUGCAGCUGGGGAUGGGAGUGGGAACAGAGAGCAAACAUUUUGGGAUGAUGGAAACAUUCUAAAACUGGAUUGUGAUUUUGGUUACACAACUGUAUACAUUUACUAAAAUCAAUGAACAGAACACUUUUAAUGGGUAAGCCUUAAGGCAUGUGAAUUAUACACCAAUAAAGCUAUUUUUUUUAAAAAAAAGAGAGAGAGAGAACGAGAGCUACAUGGCAGCCCCAGGGCAAUAGCUCUCAGAUCUCCCUUAGAGAAAGAACUUUCUCUUCCACAGCAAUGAGUGCAGGUAGCUAACACUGACCAACCUGCAUCUGGUAGUUCAUUUAAGGUCGGCCUUGGCUUUCAAGUUAAGGCCAUGGUCUUUCUCUGCAGUCCCCAGCCAAUACGUGGGCACAGAAAGGCACAGGGCAUGGCUGAUUCAGCCCAACAUGAGGCUCCACACCCUAGAACUCCCUGUGGAGUUGGCCGAUACUGCCUGUGACCUGCAAUGUGGUCUAAGCUGUCAGACCUCCACAGUGGCCAGAAGGUUUUCCAUACCUGAGCCUGCUUCUACCCACUUUUAUUUUUCCCAGGAGUCACGCUUAGUCAUCUCUUGCUCUUUGAACUCCAUGUCUGUAUCAGCUACCCAGAGGACCCAUCAGACAGAAAGUAAUAUGCAGAUAACAGCCCAGGGGAAUCUGGGCAGCACUGUGAAACCAACAUUUCUUCAGUGAAACCUAGAACAAAAGUGGAAUAAAUAAAAACUAACUGUCUCAUUUCAGCA